GCCUCUCCUGACUCUUCACCUGGACUCUGAGUCGUCUUGGUCCCAGGAGCCAGUAGUGAAGGCAACAGUCUGCCCACCUGUGGACACCAGAUCCUGGGAGCUCCUGGUUAGCAAGUGAGAUCUCUGGGAUGUCAGUGAGGCUGGUUGAAGACCAGAGGUAAACUGCAGAGGUCACCACCCCCACCAUGUCCCAGGUGAUGUCCAGCCCACUGCUGGCAGGAGGCCAUGCUGUCAGCUUGGCGCCUUGUGAUGAGCCCAGGAGGACCCUGCACCCAGCACCCAGCCCCAGCCUGCCACCCCAGUGUUCUUACUACACCACGGAAGGCUGGGGAGCCCAGGCCCUGAUGGCCCCCGUGCCCUGCAUGGGGCCCCCUGGCCGACUCCAGCAAGCCCCACAGGUGGAGGCCAAAGCCACCUGCUUCCUGCCGUCCCCUGGUGAGAAGGCCUUGGGGACCCCAGAGGACCUUGACUCCUACAUUGACUUCUCACUGGAGAGCCUCAAUCAGAUGAUCCUGGAACUGGACCCCACCUUCCAGCUGCUUCCCCCAGGGACUGGGGGCUCCCAGGCUGAGCUGGCCCAGAGCACCAUGUCAAUGAGAAAGAAGGAGGAAUCUGAAGCCUUGGACAUAAAGUACAUCGAGGUGACCUCCGCCAGAUCAAGGUGCCACGAUGGCCCCCAGCACUGCUCCAGCCCCUCUGUCACCCCGCCCUUCGGCUCCCUUCGCAGUGGUGGCCUCCUCCUUUCCAGAGACGUCCCCCGAGAGACACGAAGCAGCAGUGAGAGCCUCAUCUUCUCUGGGAACCAGGGCAGGGGGCACCAGCGCCCUCUGCCCCCCUCAGAGGGUCUCUCCCCUCGACCCCCAAAUUCCCCCAGCAUCUCAAUCCCUUGCAUGGGGAGCAAGGCCUCGAGCCCCCAUGGUUUGGGCUCCCCGCUGGUGGCUUCUCCAAGACUGGAGAAGCGGCUGGGAGGCCUGGCCCCACAGCGGGGCAGCAGGAUCUCUGUGCUGUCAGCCAGCCCAGUGUCUGAUGUCAGCUAUAUGUUUGGAAGCAGCCAGUCCCUCCUGCACUCCAGCAACUCCAGCCAUCAGUCAUCUUCCAGAUCCUUGGAAAGUCCAGCCAACUCUUCCUCCAGCCUCCACAGCCUUGGCUCAGUGUCCCUGUGUACAAGACCCAGUGACUUCCAGGCUCCCAGAAACCCCACCCUAACCAUGGGCCAACCCAGAACACCCCACUCUCCACCACUGGCCAAAGAACAUGCCAGCAGCUGCCCCCCAUCCAUCACCAACUCCAUGGUGGACAUACCCAUUGUGCUGAUCAACGGCUGCCCAGAACCAGGGUCUUCUCCACCCCAGCGGACCCCAGGACACCAGAACUCCGUUCAACCUGGAGCUGCUUCUCCCAGCAACCCCUGUCCAGCCACCAGGAGCAACAGCCAGACCCUGUCAGAUGCCCCCUUUACCACAUGCCCAGAGGGUCCCGCCAGGGACAUGCAGCCCACCAUGAAGUUCGUGAUGGACACAUCUAAAUACUGGUUUAAGCCAAACAUCACCCGAGAGCAAGCAAUCGAGCUGCUGAGGAAGGAGGAGCCAGGGGCUUUUGUCAUAAGGGACAGCUCUUCAUACCGAGGCUCCUUCGGCCUGGCCCUGAAGGUGCAGGAGGUUCCCGCGUCUGCUCAGAGUCGACCAGGUGAGGACAGCAAUGACCUCAUCCGACACUUCCUCAUCGAGUCGUCUGCCAAAGGAGUGCAUCUCAAAGGAGCAGAUGAGGAGCCCUACUUUGGGAGCCUCUCUGCCUUCGUGUGCCAGCAUUCCAUCAUGGCCCUGGCCCUGCCCUGCAAACUCACCAUCCCACAGAGAGAACUGGGAGGUGCAGAUGGGGCCUCGGACUCUACAGACAGCCCAGCCUCCUGCCAGAAGAAAUCUGCGGACCUUGAAGAUGGAGGUGUGGGGAGGAGAGCAGCCGUUAAGUGUGGACAGAAGGAUGUUUUCCUGGGCACCUCUACACACAGGGCAACAUCCCCUCCCCUGCCCCAUGCUGGAGGGCCAGGGGCCAGGGCGAUGCAAAGCCACAGAAGAUCCCAAAGCCCUCUGGGGUUGGCCUCAAACUGUGAUCACCCACACACCCACUUUCUGUUGGGUGGCGGCUCUAAGAGGAGCUCCACUGGAUUCCUGAACAGGAGACUCACCCCCUCCCCUGGCCCUGGGCAGAGGGAGAACCUGGGCCCUGGGUCAGUGGCCCCAGCGCAGUGUCUGCCUCCCACAGGCUGCCACACCCUGUACCUGAGCUCAGUGAGCGUGGAGACCCUGACUGGAGCCCUGGCCGUGCAGAAAGCCAUCUCCACCACCUUUGAGAGGGACAUCCUCCCCACGCCCACCGUGGUCCACUUCAAAGUCACAGAGCAGGGCAUCACUCUGACUGAUGUCCAGAGGAAGGUGUUUUUCCGGCGCCAUUACCCACUCACCACCCUCCGCUUCUGUGGUAUGGACCCUGAGCAACGGAAGUGGCAGAAGUACUGCAAACCCUCCUGGAUCUUUGGGUUUGUGGCCAAGAGCCAGACAGAGCCUCAGGAGAACGUAUGCCACCUCUUUGCGGAGUAUGACAUGGUCCAGCCAGCCUCGCAGGUCAUCGGCCUGGUGACUGCUCUGCUGCAGGACGCAGAAAGGAUGUAGGGGAGAGACUGCCUGUGCACCUAACCAACACCUCCAGGGGCUCGCUAAGGAGCCCCCCUCCACCCCCUGAAUGGGUGUGGCUUGUGGCCAUAUUGACAGACCAAUCUAUGGGACUAGGGGGAUUGGCAUCAAGUUGACACCCUUGAACCUGCUAUGGCCUUCAGCAGUCACCAUCAUCCAGACCCCCCGGGCCUCAGUUUCCUCAAUCAUAGAAGAAGACCAAUAGACAAGAUCAGCUGUUCUUAGAUGCUGGUGGGCAUUUGAACAUGCUCCUCCAUGAUUCUGAAGCAUGCACACCUCUGAAGACCCCUGCAUGAAAAUAACCUCCAAGGACCCUCUGACCCCAUCGACCUGGGCCCUGCCCACACAACAGUCUGAGCAAGAGACCUGCAGCCCCUGUUUCGUGGCAGACAGCAGGUGCCUGGCGGUGACCCACGGGGCUCCUGGCUUGCAGCUGGUGAUGGUCAAGAACUGACUACAAAACAGGAAUGGAUAGACUCUAUUUCCUUCCAUAUCUGUUCCUCUGUUCCUUUUCCCACUUUCUGGGUGGCUUUUUGGGUCCACCCAGCCAGGAUGCUGCAGGCCAAGCUGGGUGUGGUAUUUAGGGCAGCUCAGCAGGGGGAACUUGUCCCCAUGGUCAGAGGAGACCCAGCUGUCCUGCACCCCCUUGCAGAUGAGUAUCACCCCAUCUUUUCUUUCCACUUGGUUUUUAUUUUUAUUUUUUUUUGAGACAGAGUCUCACUGUCACCCAGGCUGAACUGCAGUGGUGUGAUCUAGGCUCACUGCAACCUCCACCUCCCAGGUUCAAGCAAUUAUCCUGCCUCAGGCUCCCAAGUAGCUGGGAUUACAGGCAUGUGCAACUCACCCAGCUAAUUUUGUAUUUUUAGUAGAGACAGGGUUUCACCAUGUUGGCCAGGCUGGUCUUGAACUCCUGACCGCAGGUAAUCCACCUGCUUCGGCCUCCCAAAGUGCUGGGAUUACAGGCGCAAGCCACCCAGCCCAGCUUCUUUCCAUUCCUUGAUAGGCGAGUAUUCCAAAGCUGGUAUCGUAGCUGCCCUAAUGUUGCAUAUUAGGCGGCGGGGGCAGAGAUAAGGGCCAUCUCUCUGUGAUUCUGCCUCAGCUCCUGUCUUGCUGAGCCCUCCCCCAACCCACGCUCCAACACACACACACACACACACACACACACACACACACACACACACACACACACACACACACGCCCCUCUACUGCUAUGUGGCUUCAACCAGCCUCACAGCCACACGGGGGAAGCAGAGAGUCAAGAAUGCAAAGAGGCCGCUUCCCUAAGAGGCUUGGAGGAGCUGGGCUCUAUCCCACACCCACCCCCACCCCACCCCCACCCAGCCUCCAGAAGCUGGAACCAUUUCUCCCGCAGGCCUGAGUUCCUAAGGAAACCACCCUACCGGGGUGGAAGGGAGGGUCAGGGAAGAAACCCACUCUUGCUCUACGAGGAGCAAGUGCCUGCCCCCUCCCAGCAGCCAGCCCUGCCAAAGUUGCAUUAUCUUUGGCCAAGGCUGGGCCUGACGGUUAUGAUUUCAGCCCUGGGCCUGCAGGAGAGGCUGAGACCAGCCCACCCAGCCAGUGGUCGAGCACUGCCCCGCCGCCAAAGUCUGCAGAAUGUGAGAUGAGGUUCUCAAGGUCACAGGCCCCAGUCCCAGCCUGGGGGCUGGCAGAGGCCCCCAUAUACUCUGCUACAGCUCCUAUCAUGAAAAAUAAAAUGUUUGUCUUUGCAAAA